GAAGUUAAACCCUCGGAGCUGGCCUCGGACUGCUGGGGCGUUACCCCUUCGGCCACCCCCGCUGACCAUGGCAGUGUUUCAUGACGAGGUGGAAAUCGAGGACUUCCAAUAUGACGAGGACUCGGAGACGUAUUUCUAUCCCUGCCCAUGUGGAGAUAACUUCUCCAUCACCAAGGAAGAUUUGGAGAAUGGGGAAGACGUGGCAACGUGUCCUAGCUGCUCUCUCAUUAUAAAAGUGAUUUAUGACAAAGAUCAGUUUGUGUGUGGAGAAACAGUCCCAGCCCCUUCAGCCAACAAAGAAUUAGUUAAAUGCUGAAGAAGCCUUCAGGAAUCCAAAUCCUGAACAUUUGGAAUGAGCCCAGAUAGAAAUAUCGAAUGCAAAGCUACUGGCUUCACAGAGACAACCAUUUAUGAUUUGCUGUUCUGUAAGAGUGUGGAUUCUUUCUAUCAACUGCUGAUAUCAUCUUCAGGAAGCAAGUCCAUAACAUGACAUAUCUGGAUUUUGUGCUUAGAACCUUAAAUUGGAAGCAUUCUUAAUUAUGCAUCUAAAUUUAAAAGAAGAUAAUUUCAAAACAGUGCUUUCUUUCCCUUGGUUUCAUCAUUUUCAUAUCUUAAACCAAAUUACUUCGGUAUCUGACAACAGCAUCAUCUACCUCAGUCAUUAGGAUUUCUUAAUAAAAAAGAGAUUGUAUUUUUGACUUGGUUAUUAAGAUUAUUAAAAUUAGCCCUUCCUUUGAAAUAUGACAUCAGCUUUGCUGUUCUAAAUUUAAAAUUAGUUGCUUCAUCAGUACCACACUUCCAGUUUCUAUACCAAGCCAGUCUCCUCAGUUUUCCCAUUAGAAUGGACAUGUUCUGUUCAGCGUGUCAUUUCUGUAAUGCUUCAUGCAGAGAGUUUGGUCAUAGUAUUAAAGAGAAAAUACAGUGAGGUCACAAUGUCUCCAGAGCUAAAAGUUAGUGAACAAGAAAGAAAGUCCAAAAUGAAGUGAUGAAAGAAUGAGGACUUUUCUUAUAUUCUGCAUAUUCCUUGGAAGUCAGGACAAGAUGAAAAGAAAAACAUCCAAAAGAAGUGAAAUUGGUGACAGAAUGAGAGGAGCAAAGCAUACCAGUGUAGUAAGUGGAAUGUUUGAAUGACUUUGCCAGGUCAGAGCAAGUAAUAUUUCUGUAUCUGAGUUUUUGUUUGUGUUUUGAUAAGGCUAAUGAAAUUGCAUUCCAGGUAGGGGUUAACGUCAAAUUUCCAUGGCUGGUAGCUGUGCUUUUGGCAUAUCACAGUGUUGUGUCACUACUACAAGGUAAAGCAUCUACAGCGGAGAAUGAGCUUGAAAAUGAGAGACCUAUUGUGAAUAAAUAUGCCCAUGAGAGCAUAUUUAAUAAGCCUCUAUAACAUGCAGCCAAACCAGACAUUCACUCCUGCAGAGAAAUGUUGCCCUGGAGAAAAAGAAAUAUAUAAAGAUAGGCUAUCACCCUUCUUUUGCUGCAGUACUAAGCAUAGCAAGAAAUUAGAAUCAUUUACAUUGGAAAUUUGAAAAUUCCCUUUAUAUACACAACUUUACUGUGUAUAAAUAAAAAAUAUUUAUUAAUGCAGUGAUGUCCGUCAGGUUGUUUUAGGAAUGGCUUCUGCAAUUAGAAAAAUAGCUUGCUAGAAUGUAAAUGUUCUGUUACUGGUAAAUGUACUGCACACAUUCAUUGGACGUUAAAACAAGUGAGUAGCCUUUUUUACCUGCCAGCAGCAUGGCUGUGUGCAGCCACUAGGCUGAGACAAUAAAUUACCAAAAAUUAUAAUGUACCGAGCUGAAAAUGCUCAGUACAUUAUGUGGCAUAUUCUGGAUGUGAUGAGAAAUCUCAUUGCCAUUUGGGACACUGACAUCCCAGAAGUAAUCCACAACUGCUUUGCAAAAGCAAAGUGACUGCUCAGAUGAACAGAGCAGAGUACUCACUCACUAUGGUGGCAUCAGCUGCAAAGCAAAAUGAACUGUCCCAUGAUCAUGUUGAUGGUUUUCUAGAUACUGCCAACAUGUUAGCUCUUUCUGAUGCUGAUGAGUUUCAAACACGAACAGACACCCUUGAUGUGGGUUUGCUAAGAACAUAGAAGAACAGGAAGAAAAGUUGCCAGGUUCACACAUCCCAGGAAAAAAGAAGCAUAAAAAGCAUUAGCAGUCAGUGACUGAUGAUAAUGCUGCAAUAAUGGGAAUGGUUUUGUUUCUAAACCAAAUUAUUUCUAAAUCAAAUCAUUUAUUGCUUUGUUUCUAAAGCAAUUGAGUCACUAAGUUUGUGAACUGUAGGAGAACACAUCAAGAUUGAAUCCUGUGUUAAGCAGAAGGUAAAACCAGAGCCAGGCGCAGUGGCUCGUGCCUGUAAUCCCAGCUACUCAGGAAGCUAAGGCAGGAGGAUCAUGUGAGGCCAGGAGUUCAAGACUAGCCUGGGCAACAUAGAAAGACCCUGUCUCUAAAAAAUCUUCUUUUAAUUAGCAAGGUGUGGGGCCUUGAGCAAAUUGCUUGGGCCCAGGAGUUUGAGGCUGUGGUGAGCUGUGAUCACACCACUGCGUUCCAGCCUGUGUGACAGGGCAAGACCUCAUGCCUAAAAAAUAAAGAGAAAGCAGAGUAAAACUGGACUCUGAGAUACGACUAAAGUUCUGUGUGAUACGUGUGCCUUAUUUAGCUCAAGACAUUCCUGGAGCACCUAUAAAAACUGACUUGUAAUCCAGGCUAUGUCUCUUUUUAGCUUCGUAAUCUUUGGCAAGGCCAUUGGAUUCUUCAGCUGUACAAUUAGGAGACUCGAUCAGGUGAUUGCCUUUCUCAGCUGUCAGUUCUCUAAUUUCAGGCUUGGUAGCUUGUAGGAACUGAAAUUGCAAUUAAAACCUUUAUAAACUCAAACUAAAUCAUGAAUUACAGAAAAAGUCCAUUCUUCCAAAACUUGAUGUUACCACACUUACAAGUUUAAAAUAUGAAGUCGACUGUUUAAAGGAUUCUGCAUAUAUUCUAGUGUGCACAUUCAGAAACAUUUUUCUUGGAAAAAGUACCCAACAUUUUUUAUAACUGCACAUAUUAAUUUAUUGCCAGAAUAAAUUGCAUUGCAUGCUAAAUAAAGUCAGAUAAUUCAAAUCCAUUUGCUUUUAUGUAGUUUUUCUUCUAAAUGUCAACAUUUUGAAUUAAAAUGUUUAUGAUUUUAUAUGAGGUAGAAAUCUUAACUGCUUUGGGGUAUUGUUAAUAGACUUUUUGUUAUGGACAGUAGUUUUUAAAUAAGGAAAUUGCCAAUUUCUACAGUUUGGGCUCUGGAUUUCUAUUGUUUGGGAAAAAAAUAACUGAGUCAAGUGGUAGUAAGACAAAGUUGACAUUCUUAGAUGAGUAACUCAGUUUAUUACAAGGAAAGAAAACUGAUUGUUUAAGGCUGAUGAUCAAUUCUUGGAGUGGUUUCAGAGCCCAGCUCUGGUCAGAAGACAAUUUGAAUCUUAGUUCCUCCACUGUGAUCUCCGAGAAGUUACUUAAUAAUUAUAUUCUGGUUUGUGAAAUCUGGAUCAUAGUACCUCUUUGACAGGGUUGCUGUGUGAACCCAUUCAUUCUGCAAUUAGAAAAAUAGCUGUCAUGUGCUAUGCACUAGGCAAAGAAGUACCUGUCACAUGCUAGGCACUAGGGGAAGAAGAUUCGGUUUCUACAUUUGGAAACUUAGUGGAACUAGAAGAGACAGAAGCAAGAUUACAGAUGAGUUAGAGCCCCCAAGGAAACAAACCAGGUGAUGUGGGAGAGAGUAACUGGGUCAGGUGACUUUUUAAGGGAGUCUGAGCUCUGGCACUUUUUCUAAGACCUGAAGGAUGAGAAGGAAACAGCCUUGUGAAAAUGAUUAAAUGAGCUAGUAUCUAUAAAACAUGACAGCUAAUGCCUGUCAUGUGCAAAAAAUGGUUAACUAUUCUAACUCCGAAAGGAAUUAAACAUUGUUUUGCGCUUUCUCCUAGUCCAUGUUCUGCUGCUGUAACAAUACCUGAGACUGGAUAAUUUAUCAAGAAUAAAGGUUAAUUUGGCUCAUGA